AAGCAGAACCCAUCAGGAAGUGCACAGGCGUCCGGCGUGCUCCUCCCUCCCUGCAGCCCCGGGCAGCAUCUCCCAGAGGCUCCGCGGCCCAGGCUCCUGGUGUGUCUGCAGUGCAGGUGGCUCCUGGAAGACCCUCAGCCUGCCUGCUGAGGCCAUGUCGGACUACGAGAACGAUGACGAGUGCUGGAGCGUCCUGGAGGGCUUCCGGGUGACGCUCACCUCGGUCAUCGACCCCUCACGCAUCACACCUUACCUGCGGCAGUGCAAGGUCCUGAACCCCGAUGAUGAGGAGCAGGUGCUCAGCGACCCCAACCUGGUCAUCCGCAAACGGAAAGUGGGUGUGCUCCUGGACAUCCUGCAGCGGACCGGCCACAAGGGCUACGUGGCCUUCCUCGAGAGCCUGGAGCUCUACUACCCGCAGCUGUACAAGAAGGUCACAGGCAAGGAGCCGGCCCGCGUCUUCUCCAUGAUCAUCGACGCGUCCGGGGAGUCAGGCCUGACUCAGCUGCUGAUGACUGAGGUCAUGAAGCUGCAGAAGAAGGUGCAGGACCUGACCGCGCUGCUGAGCUCCAAAGAUGACUUCAUCAAGGAGCUGCGGGUGAAGGACAGCCUGCUGCGCAAGCACCAGGAGCGUGUGCAGAGGCUCAAGGAGGAGUGCGAGGCCGGCAGCCGCGAGCUCAAGCGCUGCAAGGAGGAGAACUACGACCUGGCCAUGCGCCUGGCGCACCAGAGUGAGGAGAAGGGCGCCGCGCUCAUGCGGAACCGUGACCUGCAGCUGGAGAUUGACCAGCUCAAGCACAGCCUCAUGAAGGCCGAGGACGACUGCAAGGUGGAGCGCAAGCACACGCUGAAGCUCAGGCACGCCAUGGAGCAGCGGCCCAGCCAGGAGCUGCUGUGGGAGCUGCAGCAGGAGAAGGCCCUGCUCCAGGCCCGGGUGCAGGAGCUGGAGGCCUCCGUCCAGGAGGGGAAGCUGGACAGGAGCAGCCCCUACAUCCAGGUACUGGAGGAGGACUGGCGGCAGGCGCUGCGGGACCACCAGGAGCAGGCCAACACCAUCUUCUCCCUGCGCAAGGACCUCCGCCAGGGCGAGGCCCGACGCCUCCGGUGCAUGGAGGAGAAGGAGAUGUUCGAGCUGCAGUGCCUGGCACUACGUAAGGACUCCAAGAUGUACAAGGACCGCAUCGAGGCCAUCCUGCUGCAGAUGGAGGAGGUCGCCAUUGAGCGGGACCAGGCCAUAGCCACGCGGGAGGAGCUGCACGCACAGCACGCCCGGGGCCUGCAGGAGAAGGACGCGCUGCGCAAGCAGGUGCGGGAGCUGGGCGAGAAGGCGGAUGAGCUGCAGCUGCAGGUGUUCCAGUGUGAGGCGCAGCUACUGGCCGUGGAGGGCAGGCUCAGGCGGCAGCAGCUGGAGACGCUCGUCCUGAGCUCCGACCUGGAAGAUGGCUCACCCAGGAGGUCCCAGGAGCUCUCACUCCCCCAGGACCUGGAGGACACCCAGCUCUCAGACAAAGGCUGCCUUGCCGGCGGGGGGAGCCCGAAACAGCCCUUUGCAGCUCUGCACCAGGAGCAGGUUUUGCGGAACCCCCAUGACGCAGGCCUGAGCAGCGGGGAGCCGCCCGAGAAGGAGCGGCGGCGCCUCAAAGAGAGUUUUGAGAACUACCGCAGGAAGCGCGCCCUCAGGAAGAUGCAGAAAGGAUGGCGGCAGGGGGAGGAGGACCGGGAGAACACCACGGGCAGCGACAACACCGACACUGAGGGCUCCUAGCCGCAGCAGCGCAGGCCCCGACCAGGGCACACCCACCGGCCCGGCCUCCUGCCACCCGGGGGUGCCGACGCCCUGGGGCGCAGACUUCCCCGAGCCGUCGCUGACUUGGCCUGGAACGAGGAAUCUGGUGCCCUGAAAGGCCCAGCCGGACUGCCGGGCAUUGGGGCCGUUUGUUAAGCGGCACUCAUUUUGCGGAGGCCAUGCGGGUGCUCACCACCCCCAUGCACACGCCAUCUGUGUAACUUCAGGAUCUGUUCUGUUUCACCAUGUAACACACAAUACAUGCAUGCAUUGUAUUAGUGUUAGAAAACACAGCUGCGUAAAUAAACAGCACGGGUGACCCGCA